CUUCCAGAAAUCUUUCAUGGUCUAUAAUACAGCAGAGAUGUGGCCUGGACUUUGCUUUGUUCCCAGGAGAUCAAAUCUUUUGAGGUCAAAACAAAGAAACUUGAAAUAUUGUAGAUAUAAGUAUGACCAGGGGGAACCCAGAUACCAGAAUCUAACUCAUAAUAUCCAAUGUGUCAUAUAUUUACCUAUUUUCUCUUUAAAUUUUUUUUUAACUUCUAGCUCAACAUUAUUGAAGAGGAAUAAAUUUUUUUUGAACUUCUAGUUCAACAUUAUUGAAGAGGAAUAUAAUGUAUUUCCACAUCUUCCAAAGAACAAAAAGGAGAGUGGAAGAAGGAGAGAGAGAAAGGACGAGACAUGAACCACACAAUGGUCACAGAGUUUGUCCUCCUGGGCCUUUCUGAUGAUCCUGACCUUCAGAUUGUGAUUUUUCUCUUUUUAUUUAUCACGUAUAUAUUAAGUGUUACUGGAAACCUGACUAUCAUCACCCUAACCUUUGUGGACUCCCAUCUGCAGACACCUAUGUAUUUCUUCCUCCGGAACUUCUCUUUCUUAGAAAUCUCAUUUACAACCGUAUGCAUCCCCAGAUUUCUGGGGGCAAUUAUCACCAGGAAUAAGACUAUUUCCUAUAACAACUGUGCAGCCCAACUCUUUUUCUUUAUCUUCAUGGGGGUGACUGAAUUUUACAUUUUAACUGCCAUGUCCUAUGACCGCUAUGUUGCCAUCUGCAAGCCCCUUCAUUACACAUCCAUCAUGAACAGGAAACUCUGCACUCUACUUGUGCUGUGUGCCUGGCUAAGUGGGUUUCUGACCAUUUUCCCACCCCUUAUGCUUCUCCUCCAGCUGGAUUACUGUGCUUCCAACGUCAUUGAUCACUUUGCAUGUGACUAUUUUCCCCUCUUACAACUAUCUUGUUCAGAUACAUGGCUCCUAGAAGUAAUUGGUUUUUACUUUGCUUUGGUUACUUUGCUGUUCACUUUGGCAUUAGUGAUUUUAUCUUACAUGUACAUUAUCAGGACCAUUUUGAGAAUCCCGUCUGCCAGUCAAAGAAAAAAGGCUUUCUCCACUUGUUCUUCUCACAUGAUUGUCAUUUCCAUUUCUUAUGGAAGCUGUAUAUUCAUGUAUGCUAAUCCAUCUGCAAAAGAAAAGGCAUCAUUGACAAAAGGAAUAGCUAUUCUCAAUACAUCUGUUGCCCCCAUGCUGAACCCCUUCAUUUACACUCUGAGAAACCAGCAAGUAAAACAAGCCUUCAAAAAUGUGGUCCACAAAGUUGUGUUUUAUGCAAAUCAAUGA